GUAGAGUGCGGGCACCUGGUGGUCUCAGGGAAGCGGGCCUGGGACCGGGGCGUGUAGGAAGCAGCGAGGGGCUCAGAACCACCUUUCCGGGUUCACGACCAGCCUCUCUGGGUGUUCCACCUGGGCAGCUGCUGGAGACUAGAAAACAUCCCUCACACGUCACAGAGGCACGGUUUCCCUCCAGCGGUGAAAUCCGCCCCAGCCUCCAGCAAGAGCAGGGCUUAGGCCUGGGGUCCUGGGGUCCUGCUCUCAGCUGGCACCUCACCCCAGACACACUCCCUGCUGCCCCCAGGGGCCUGUUCUCGAGGGAUUCCCGAGGAGUGCGCUCGUGAAGUCAUAUCUGCCUCACGCCCAAAAGGGCAACCCUUCCCGGGCAGAUAUGACUUCACCACGUACCUGUGUGGCCCUGGGGAACUCAGCAACUGCUUAGCUCUCAUUUGUGGGUCGUCCAAGGCCCAAGUGGCUGUGACAACCUGAGAUCUCCAGGGUUGCUGGGAGCCGGGGCAGCAACCAGGGGUGCGGCUUGCUCUCCAGGGAGCUGCGGCAGAGCCUGGGGCCACAGCUGCACUCAGCCGGUGCACCCACGGACAGAGGGUCAGACUCGGCUCAGCACUGGGCUCAAGCCCUGGAUGAGAACAAGAACCAAGCUUCUUAGCCUCAGGCUCCAUCUGGGAAAUGGAGUGUCACUUGUGGAGUCCAUGAGCUCACCAGGGACAGGAUCCCGGGUCCACAGCGAGGGCCCACAGCGUGGGAGGAGGGCUGCUCCUCCGGGCCCAGGCCUGGGCGCCCUCCUCCCAUGCUGACCAGCCAGCUGGCCUCGUCUUUGCUCCCGGAUAAUGAGCACCCAUGUGGCAGGCCUGGGCCUGGACAAGAUGAAGCUGGGCAAUCCCCAGUCCUUCCUGGACCAGGAGGAGGCAGAUGACCAGCAGCUGCUGGAACCAGAGGCGUGGAAGACCUACACCGAGCGCCGCAAUGCCCUGCGUGAGUUCCUGACCUCGGACCUGAGUCCGCACCUGCUCAAGCGCCACCACGCCCGCAUGCAGCUGCUGCGUAAGUGCUCCUACUACAUCGAGGUCCUGCCCAAGCACCUGGCCCUGGGCGACCAGAACCCGCUGGUGCUGCCUAGCGCCUUGUUCCAGCUCAUCGACCCCUGGAAGUUCCAGCGCAUGAAGAAGGUGGGCACAGCUCAGACCAAGAUCCAGCUCCUGCUGCUCGGGGACCUGUUGGAACAGCUCGACCAUGGCCGUGCUGAGCUGGAUGCCCUGCUCCGGUCGCCAGACCCACGGCCCUUCCUGGCCGACUGGGCGCUGGUGGAGCGGCGGCUGGCGGACGUGUCGGCCGUCAUGGACAGCUUCCUGACCAUGAUGGUGCCGGGGCGGCUACACGUCAAGCACCGCCUGGUGUCUGAUGUCAGUGCCACCAAGAUCCCGCACAUCUGGCUCAUGCUGAGCACCAAGAUGCCUGUCGUGUUUGACCGAAAGGCGUCGGCGGCUCACCAGGACUGGGCCCGGCUGCGCUGGUUCGUCACCAUCCAGCCAGCCACAUCGGAGCAGUAUGAGUUGCGCUUCAGGCUGCUGGACCCGCGGACACAGCAGGAGUGCGCCCAGUGUGGCGUCAUCCCCGUGGCUGCCUGCACCUUCGACGUCCGAAACCUGCUGCCCAACCGAUCCUAUAAGUUCACCAUCAAGAGGGCCGAGACCUCCACGCUGGUGUACGAGCCCUGGAGGGACAGCCUCACCCUGCACACCAAGCCGGAGCCCCUGGAGGGGCCCGCCCUCAGCCACUCUGUCUGAGAGAUGAUUUUCUAAUAUUUAUCCACUAAUAAAGAAGAGUGUAAAUGCACAUAUGGAAUUAAAGAAGCAAACCUA